GGGCAGCCGGACCGGGGUGACCGUGCGAGGACUGUGUGCGAUGUGACCCUGUCUUGGGGAGCUGUGCGGGGACUUUGUGUGCGGUGUGACCCCUAUCGGGGGGCGACUUUGCAGGGACUGUGUAUGCAGUGCGACCCCUCUGGGAGUGUCUGCAGGAUACUGUGUGUGCGCUGUGACCCACAUCAGGGGGUUACCCCCAUCUUGGGGUGACCCCUGUUAGGCGGAGACUGUGUGCGUUGUGACCCCUAAGGGUGACUGUGCAGAGACUGUGUGUGCAGAUGUGACCUCGUGAUUGUGUGGGGACUGUGAUUUCAGGUGUGACCCCCAUCUUGGGUUGACCUCUGUCUGGGGAGGACUGUGCGUCUGUCGGGACUCCCAUUUGUGAGUGACUCUGCAGUGUGACCAGGGUCCAGGGGUGACUGGAUGUGCAACUGGGACCCUUGAUUGGGUGACUGCGUGAGCCGCUGGUUCUGAGACCUGUGGCCGGGGUAGUUCUAGGCCCUUUGCCUGUAUGCCUGGCUGUGCGAUGUGAGAUGUGACUGUUGCUGACCUGCCGUCCGGGGACUGUGCCAGCGUGAGACAGGCAUCUGGGAGUGCCCCUACAAACGUGUGAGAUUGUUUCCCCGCCUGCCGCCUCUGGAGUUCUGUCUGUAGGCGUGCCCGUGUCACUGUGUGACGGUGACCGAGCGUGCUGUGGGCUCUGUGUGGCUGUGUUUCACGUCUGUGCGUGCAGCCUUAGUCUGGCUUUUCCUUUCUGUAACAUCACUCAGGCCUGUGUGUUUAUGUGCAUCUAUCUUUCUGUGUGGCUGUGACCCAUUCUGGGUGAUUGCAUAGGUGCAUUCCUGGGUUGCGUGUCCUGGCACUGUGCGCGUUUUUGUGGGUCUGUGUGUGGCCCAGGUCCGUUUGCCUGGCCACUUUUUCCUCUGGGGUUGAUUGAGGGCACUGUUGCCCUCUUAGCCUGCAGGGUUGGCCUGGCUUGUCCUAGGCUGGGGCCUUGGGCCUCUGAGCAGGUCAGCCCUCUGUAGCUGCAGGGAUGACCCUCUGGUCGCGCAAUCUUGCCCACCAUCUCUUGAAGAACCCGUCAAGGCCUCUGGUCUAAACUCUUACCUAUAACAAGGCUGAGUGUCCGCCUGCAGACCCUUAGCUGUGUUUAGAGAAGACUGGAGGAGCGGCCCUGCGGUCCCAGGCCCAGGAAGUUCCGCAGCCAGCAUCUGGGCUCUUCAGCCCCUUUCUUUGUGGGAGGGAGUGGGGGAAGUUGACUGAUAACACGGGGGAGGUUUGUGUGUCUGAGAGAGACAAGAGAAUAAUGUUUGCAUUUGGCUUGACAGCCCUGUCUCCUGGUAGGGUAGUUCUUCAGCCUUGUUUUGCUGGGAUUGGCAGGGACAUUUUCAGAGUGGCUGGGAAGUUGAACCUUCACAGCCCCCUCCUUGGAGAGGAGAGGCCAUUCAUGAGUUAUCUAUACACAGAAGGUUCUAGUAAUCCCCCUCUACACGCUGAUUAGAGGCAAAAGAACACUGGCGAUCAAUAGCCUGCUACUGAGAAGUUAGGUUGCAGGAGCGCCUUUCCUUCCCACAGCGAGGAGGGGCUGUUUUCUGUUCCGGUCACUGCUGUCUGGCAAUUUAUGCACUUAAUCUCAGGUUCUCAUCACAAAAGUUUAUGUGAGGUAAGGGGAGAGGUUGGCUUCAGGCUGAACCUGUCAGCCCAGAUUUCUGAUUCAAAACCCCAUGUUCCUAGAGUUACUUGCAACCUAAUCUGUUCUUGUCUUACGCAUUUUAAGGUCUUAUUAUUUUUUAGUUACAUACCAUAAAUUUGCCAUUUUAAAGUGUACAAUUCAGUGGUUUUUAGUAUAUACAUGAGAUUGUGCAACCACCACCAUCUAAUUCCAGAACAUUUUCAUCCUCCCCAAAAUAGGAACCCUGUACCCGUUAGCCCUCACCUGCAGCCUCCCCCUGCCCCAUUCUCCCUAACCUUAGGCAACCACUAAUCUACUUUCUGUAUCUAUGGAUUUGCUUAUUCUGGACAUUUUAUAUAAAUGGAAUCACACCCUGUGUGGCCUUUUGUGUCUGGCUUCUUUGACUCAGCAUCACGUUUUCAAAGUUCAUGCAUAUUGUAGCAUGUGGCAGUACUUCAUUCCUUUUCAUGGCUGUAUAAUACUCCAUUGUAUGGAUGUACCACAUUUUGUUGGACAUUUGUGUUGUGUCUACUAGAUACAUUUUCAAUUAUUAUAUAAAGCAUUAUUUUUACCAAGUGCCAAUGACCCUGAUAAACAUAAAGUAAAACUCAGGCAGCUUUUAUUUGAUCAUAGCAAAGCUGCAGCAUUCAUUGCUUGGCUUUGAAUGCGCUGGGAUGUUUCCCGAAGGCAAGGCCCUCGUUCAGAUGUGUUGAGGUGAGAAGCAAGGUGGGAUGGAGACAGCAAGUGUGUAUGGGGUCAGGAGACCUAGGCCAGGCCGGUUCUGCCCUGGUCCGCCCUCGCUUGAGUUGCUUCCUGUGUGUGGGCCCUGGCUCAUCUAAAAGGACUGAAUUACCUCUUUCAUGUGUUCCUUGGCAGAUGUAGUUUCCCUGGAAUAACUGACCUGAGAUGGCCUUUCAUCUGAGAACCUCAGAGAGUGACCGAGAGUUAAAUGAUUGUGAAGUCCGUACCCCCAAGUCACGUCAUCACUCUUCAAAUUGCAACUUCAUAAUGAGUCAGACACUUAGGGCAGUGCUUUCCUGACACAGCCAGGCCUGCUGCCGGCGUGGGAAACGGGGGAUCACAGCCCUCAGUCCUAAGGCUCUCUUUUCUCUUUUAAUUUUCUUUUUUUCCCAGUCUUUGAUUAUGUCACUUAUGUCAUUUUCCUGUGAAUCUUAUCUCAGUUCCUUUGUGUGAACAGGCAGAGCACAAGAAUAGAUAAAUCAAUAAUUUUCAGGAAUGGAUCAUAACAUUGUUAUUUCUGAGAAACAUUCAAAGUGACUAAUUUUCAUGGGCAGAUCUCCAGGCACUUUUUUGGAUUGGACCAGAGUUUCUCAACCCACUGUUGAUACUUGGGACCAGAACAUUCUCUCUUGUGGGGGGACCAUCCUGUGUGUUGUGGGAUCCUGUCCUCUACCCACUAGGUGCCAGUAGUGACCUCCAGAAAAAUGCCUCCAGACAUCUUCCAAUGUCUCCUGUUGAGAGAACUUGCUCCGCAUUGAGAACCACUGGGUUAGACCCCAACAUACUCUUUGUCAAUUUGUUGCUCUUGUGACUUGUUUUGUGGUCAUUGAAGCCUUCCCUGCUCUUUCCACUUCUCCUUCAGUGUGGGGUAGGUGCCUCUGCAGAAUCUUGUAUGUACUUCAUCUUAAUAUGAUGUAGGGACUCCCAGGCCCUCUGGUGUACGCUUUUUUUUUUUUUUUGAAACGAAGUAUUGCUCUUUCACCAGGCUGGAGUGCAGUGGUGCAAUCUCGGCUCACUGCAACCUCCGCCUCCUGGGUUCAAGUGAUUCUCCUGCCUCAGCCUCCCAGGUAGCUGGGAUUACAGGUACAUGUCACCGUGCCUGGCUAAUUUUUGUAUUUUUAGUAGAGACAGCGUGUCACCUUGUUGGCUAGGCUGGUCUCGAACUCCUGACCUCAGGUGAUCCGCCCACCUCGGCCUCCUGCAGUGCUGGGAUUCCAGGUGUGAGCCACUGCGCCGGGCUGGUGUACUCAUUCUUGGUUGAAGUUGCCACCUCCUGGUGGGUGUCCCUUGCUGCCCAGGCCCCUCCCUACAUUAUCUCUGGACCCUUUUUCCUUCGCCCUUGGCUCCUGCCUCAUUUCUGUCCUCGAUCAGCCCUGCAUCUCUCCCAGCCAUCACAGCUUUCCAGGUUUCUCUUUCCCAUUCAAUGGGCGCCUCUGUGCAACAUAAAAAACAUGCCAAGUCCCAGCGGUGCGGAGUUGUUUGGGGGGUGUGUAUGUGUUUCCUUCUUAUUUUCAGUUUGCUCUCUGAAAGAAAAAAAAUAAAAAUAAGUCAUAGGUACUUCUGGAGCCCAAACUCGUGGCCUUUUAGAUUUCAGAAAAUAUUAAAUAUCUCUUUCUUGCAUUUAUAUAAAUAAACCGAUAGCCUAGGAUGUUUCGUAUCAAAUGUUUAAGUCUUUUCGAGAACCAUCAAGAGCUUUCAAGACCCACAAACAGACGGCCUGAUUCCUGGCCACCUUCCACUGUGCAAGUCUUGCCUGGGUUGGUUUUUUGAAAAUGGUGUUCAUCACUCAGCUGUUAUUGCCUGGCUCUGCGGAGGAAGUGGAUUCUCUUUAAACAUGACCCCCUCCCCUUAAAAGAGAAAAACAGGAUAAGGUCCAGAACAACCUCGGAAAGUUGAGGGCUGAGGGCUAAAAGACCGUGCUGGGUAACAACACCAGAUAGGAAAUGUUGAGCUAACAGGACUCCAUCCCCUGGACUGCGGCAGGAAUGUGGGUCAACAUUUGGAAACCUGAAAAUUCCCCCACGGAAAUGACUCCAAGGGACAGACCGGGAUUGUUGGAGGCUGGCAGCGAAGAAGAUCGAAAAUUAAACCUCAGCUUAAGUGAGAGCUUUUUCAUGGUGAAAGGCGCAGCCCUCUUCUUACAACAGGGAAGCAGCCCUCAAGGCCAGCGGAGUCUUCAGCACCCCCACAAGCAUGCAGGUGAUCUGCCUCAACAUCUUCAGGUGAUGAUCAACCUUCUGCGUUGCGAAGACAGAAUCAAGCUGGCAGUGCGCCUGGAGAGCGCCUGGGCGGACCGGGUCCGGUACAUGGUGGUGGUGUACAGCAGCGGGCGCCAGGACACCGAGGAGAAUAUCUUGCUGGGAGUGGACUUUUCCAGUAAGGAAAGUAAAAGCUGCACCAUUGGGAUGGUUCUCCGACUGUGGAGCGACACGAAAAUCCACCUUGAUGGAGAUGGUGGGUUCAGCGUGAGCACAGCAGGAAGGAUGCACAUAUUUAAGCCUGUGUCUGUCCAGGCCAUGUGGUCUGCCCUGCAGGUGCUUCACAAGGCCUGCGAAGUGGCCCGGAGGCACAACUACUUCCCCGGGGGUGUAGCUCUCAUCUGGGCUACCUACUAUGAGAGCUGCAUCAGCUCCGAGCAGAGCUGCAUCAACGAGUGGAACGCCAUGCAGGACCUGGAGUCUACGCGGCCCGACUCCCCCGCGCUAUUUGUGGACAAGCCCACUGAAGGGGAAAGGACCGAGCGCCUCAUCAAAGCCAAGCUCCGAAGCAUCAUGAUGAGCCAGGAUCUAGAAAAUGUGACUUCCAAAGAGAUUCGUAAUGAAUUAGAGAAACAGAUGAAUUGUAACUUGAAGGAACUCAAGGAAUUUAUAGACAAUGAGAUGCUACUUAUCUUGGGACAGAUGGACAAGCCCUCCCUUAUCUUCGAUCAUCUUUAUCUCGGCUCUGAAUGGAAUGCAUCCAAUCUGGAGGAACUGCAGGGCUCAGGGGUUGAUUACAUUUUAAAUGUUACCAGAGAAAUCGAUAAUUUUUUUCCUGGCUUAUUUGCAUAUCAUAACAUCCGAGUCUACGAUGAAGAGACCACAGACCUCCUCGCCCACUGGAAUGAAGCGUAUCAUUUUAUAAACAAAGCGAAGAGGAACCAUUCCAAGUGCCUGGUGCAUUGCAAAAUGGGCGUGAGUCGCUCGGCCUCCACAGUCAUAGCCUAUGCAAUGAAGGAAUUCGGCUGGCCUCUGGAAAAAGCAUAUAACUAUGUAAAGCAGAAGCGCAGCAUCACGCGCCCCAACGCGGGCUUUAUGAGGCAGCUGUCUGAGUAUGAAGGCAUCUUGGAUGCAAGCAAACAGCGGCACAACAAGCUGUGGCGUCAGCAGACAGACAGCAGCCUCCAGCAGCCUGUGGAUGACCCUGCAGGACCUGGCGACUUCUUGCCAGAGACCCCAGAUGGCACCCCGGAAAGCCAGCUGCCCUUCUUGGAUGAUGCCGCCCAGCCCGGCUUAGGGCCCCCCCUCCCCUGCUGUUUCCGGCGACUCUCAGACCCCCUUCUGCCUUCCCCUGAGGAUGAAACUGGCAGCUUGGUCCACCUGGAGGAUCCGGAGAGGGAGGCUCUGUUGGAGGAAGCUGCUCCACCUGCAGAGGUGCACAGGCCGGCCAGACAGCCCCAGCAAGGUUCCGGACUCUGUGAGAAGGAUGUGAAGAAGAAACUAGAGUUUGGGAGUCCCAAAGGUCGGAGCGGCUCCUUGCUGCAGGUGGAGGAGACGGAAAGGGAGGAGGGCCUGGGAGCAGGGAGGUGGGGGCAGCUUCCAACCCAGCUCGAUCAAAACCUGCUCAACUCGGAGAACCUAAACAACAACAGCAAGAGGAGCUGUCCCAACGGCAUGGAGGAUGAUGCUAUAUUUGGGAUCCUUAACAAAGUGAAGCCUUCCUAUAAAUCCUGUGCCGACUGCAUGUACCCUACAGCCAGCGGGGCUCCUGAGGCCUCCAGGGAGCGAUGUGAGGACCCCAAUGCUCCCGCCAUCUGCACCCAGCCAGCCUUCCUACCCCACAUCACGUCCUCCCCUGUGGCCCACUUGGCCAGCAGGUCCCGUGUUCCGGAGAAGCCAGCCUCUGGCCCAACCGAACCUCCCCCGUUCCUACCACCAGCAGGCUCCAGGAGGGCAGACACCAGUGGCCCUGGGGCUGGAGCUGCCCUAGAGCCACCAGCCAGCCUUUUGGAACCUUCCAGAGAGACCCCAAAAGUCCUGCCAAAGUCCCUCCUUUUGAAGAAUUCUCACUGUGAUAAGAACCCUCCCAGCACAGAAGUGGUAAUAAAGGAAGAAUCGUCACCCAAGAAAGAUAUGAAGCCAGCCAAGGACCUGAGGCUUCUGUUCAGUAAUGAAUCUGAGAAGCCGACAACCAACAGCUACCUGAUGCAGCACCAGGAGUCCAUCAUUCAGCUGCAGAAGGCAGGCUUGGUCCGCAAGCACACCAAAGAGCUAGAGCGGCUGAAGAGCGUGCCUGCAGACCCAGCACCUCCCUCCAGGGAUGGCCCUGCCAGCAGGCUGGAGGCCAGCAUCCCCGAGGAGAGCCAGGAUCCAGCCGCGCUCCACGAGCUGGGCCCCCUGGUUAUGCCCAGCCAGGCCGGGAGUGAUGAGAAGUCAGAGGCCGCCCCCGCUUCAUUGGAAGGAGGCUCACUGAAGAGCCCCCCUCCUUUCUUCUACCGCCUGGACCACACCAGUAGUUUCUCAAAAGACUUUCUGAAGACCAUCUGCUACACCCCCACCUCCUCUUCCAUGAGCUCCAACCUGACCCGGAGCUCCAGCAGCGAUAGCAUCCACAGUGUCCGUGGGAAGCCCGGGCUGGUGAAGCAGCGGACACAGGAGAUUGAGACCCGGCUCCGGCUGGCGGGCCUCACCGUCUCUUCCCCACUGAAGCGCUCACACUCUCUUGCCAAGCUGGGGAGUCUCACCUUCUCAACGGAAGACCUGUCCAGUGAGGCUGACCCGUCCACCGUCGCUGACUCCCAGGACACCACUUUGAGUGAAUCUUCCUUCUUGCAUGAGCCCCAGGGAACCCCGAGGGACCCAGCUGCAACCUCCAAACCAUCAGGGAAACCCGCCCCAGAAAACUUAAAGAGCCCUUCGUGGAUGAGCAAAAGCUGACCCGCCUUUUGCUGCGUCAGGCUGGGCGGAUAUUUUCAUAUGAUCCCUCCCUCACUUUCACUGUGGAUUUGGAUCGACCCCUUACAUCUUGAUUUCCCUUAAACGAGUGAAGUCAUCCUAACUUUUCCCCUACUCUUGCCAUAGAGAGGAGGAGAAGAAACUAACCAACAUGCAGCACAAGAAGGGGAGCUGUCAGUCGUGUGGCCUGGGAGAACCAGGAGCCGCCGGCCAGGAGACACAAAACUCCGCUCCCACCGUGUCUUCAAGAAGAACCAUGUUUUAGGAAGAACGUGCACACAUAGGCGCACACAUCCAGACUGUUCCCUUCGCAUCCUGCAGAAGAGUCCUGGUGGUGGCAGCCUCACCGCGGCACACGUUCUAGCUCAUUCUUGGCCUCGCAGAAAACUCUCGGAUGGCAACAUUAAGUCCUACCUCUGUUCUCGCUGCGCUUUUUAUUUUUAAAACACACGAAUGACCAAGGCUUGUUCCAGGGAAUAAUGCUCUGUCUGAAAGCGUUUUUCCAAAAAAAGAAUUUUUCGUUUUGUGUUUUGGUUGGGACCCCAGACGUGUCAAGACUUUUAACCCGACAGCCCCAAGCACUGCUGAGUAAAGUCAUCAGAUGAGUAGUCCCACGCUGUUGUUGAGCUGACUCUGUGCCCGAAUGGUGGUGCAGGCGCCCUGUCCUGGUUGUGUUGUUACGUGUUUGACCAGCACAGGGGUCCGGUGGGGAAAAUGUAUGGGUUGUUCUCAGUUGUUGCUAAUGCUGAAGUUUAAAUCUCAAGGGGAAGGGCCCACCUGCAUUGUUGAGUGUCUGCUGCUGAAACACAUGAUUGUGUUUAGGUUUGAAAUUGCUCAAGUGUCUGGCUCAGGUGGUGGUUCUGAGACACAUCGUCCUGCUGAGAGCCCAGAUGCUUAGGUCCACUAGGGCCCAUCUAGGGAAGGGAAAGGAGAUUUCAGCGGCUUCCCCGAAAGGAACGGGACUGUCGGGAUGCUUCCCGGAUGUCUACAGUUGCCCCUUCCUGCAGUGAGAUUACUGCUUCCUGUUUCCCUCCAGCUCUUCCCAGCAGCAGUGAGGGAGUAUAAGAGGGAUCUGUAGUCGCUGCCUGGCUCUGUGGGCGGCCCCUUUAAGACUCAGGUGAGCUCAGCCAGUCCCGCUGCGCCAGGCUUGAAUCAAAGGUGUCAGCAAGCUAGAUGUCAAAACAUUUCGAGAGAGAGGCAGCUUGCAGAAAAGCAGAAAGGUUGAAUUCAGGGGUCAGCAAACUAUGGCAUGUGGCCCCGUGAGCUAGGAAUGGUUUUUCCUCUUUAAGACAGGGCCUGGCUCUGUCACCUAGGCUGGAGUACAGUAGUGCAAUCAUGACUCACUGCAGCAUCAACCUCCCUGGCUCAAGCGAUGGCUUUUACCUUUUUAAGGAGUUGUAAAAAAAAGAAAUAAUAUGUGACAGAAUUCAUGUGGCCCACAAAGCCUGAGGUACUUACUGUCAGGCCCUUUGUAGAAAAAGUUGCUGACCCCUGGUUUGAUUUGCCACACAGGGCUGCUCAUGGCCCUGUAGGAAGAAACUGGGUAAAUGUGAAGCCCUCUGCCUCUCUGACACCUAAGGCCAGACCCUUCCCUCCUCCCGACCACAAGCUUUGCCAGCCCCGCACUAGCCUCACCUGUGCAGGAUGGAGUAGGUUGCGUACAUGGGGGAAGGCAGGUGAACACAGUUGGCUGAAGCUCUUCCACAAUUCCAUCUUGCCCUCAGCUGGGUCCGCCAGAUUAACUCAGUGAAACCAGAAAGCCUUCAAGGACCAGCUGAAUUCUGAAAGUGAGUGAGUGAGCCAUCAUCUUAACAUUGGCCAGAACUGUGUUCCCCAAAGCUAUUCUAGAAAGCACCCCAGGAGGGAUCUGCAGGAACAAGGCUAGUUCAUAUUUUACCUAGUGAGCACAGUUUUUGCAAAAAUCCUCCCUCCAGGACUUUGUCUCCUUGGAGUGAUUUUUAAAAAUACAUACAUUACUUUAUAGGGAGCUGUUUUCCCACUAGUGUCAAUUAAAAUCACCUUAAAAGGUGAUUAUCCACUUAUUCCUAAACCCCUGUGGGUUGUUCCCCCUUUCCCUCAGCCAACAAAAGCAUAGCCUCAAAAAAUAUCAAGUUCGGUAUGUUUUGCCAAAUCAAAUUUCAUGUGGUAGAUCAAUUUUUGUGUCAAAAUAAUCUUUUAAAUUUAGUGAUGACAGGCUUUUGUUGGUUUUUUAACCACGUCUAUGUAUGAGAAUGAUAUAUUUUUGAAAACUUUAAUUUUGAAAGCCAUAAUUUUUCUUAUCUAAAGAGUUGGGGGGUGGGGUGUGGAAUCUGGAGAGUACAAGUUGGUCUUUGGCUUCUGGCAAACUUACCCAUUCAUUUUUGGAAGCACAGCUAGCAUAUCAACAUCCAGACGAGAGCGCUGGUCCCGUCCACAGAGCAGAGUGAAGCAUUCUGGACUUGAUGCUUAAUAGCCUGGCCUGGAGAAAAGGGUAAGGUUUAUUUUUGGAAACCCAGAUCAGUUGCAUGUAAACAGAUGGCACAUGGCUAUUUAAAAUGCUGUAUGAUGGGGCCGGGCGCGGUGGCUCACGCCUGUAAUCCUAGCACUUUGGGAGGCCGAGGCAGGCGGAUCAUCUGAGGUCAGGAGUUCUAGACCAGCCUGGCCAACAUGGUGAAACCCCGUCUCUACUAAAAAUACAAAAACUUAGCUGGGUGUGGUAGUGCGUGCCUGUAAUCCUAGCUACUUAGGAGGCUGAGGCAGGAGAAUCGCUUGAACCUGGGUGGCGGAGGUUGCAAUGAGCCGAGAUCGCGCCACUGCACUCCAGCCUGGGUGCAAUGAAACUGGGAGUGAAACUCCGUCUCAAAAAAAUAAAAUGCUGUAUGAACAAGAUGAGCAUUCUGUCAGGUGUCGGGACACCUGGGCAAAGACGAAUUCAUGCUGUCUGUGAAAAGGAAGUUUGCACUGUAACAUAUGCCAUAGCUUGGCCCUUGCUUUGUAUGCAACCUUAGCUGAUGGGGAAAAUUCCAAACAUAAGUGGCACAGGAAAGAGGCAGGCAGAGGAGGCAGGGGUCUGUGCUGUGCAAGUCACUGGUUUUUUAUGACUAUCAUUUUCAUUGAAUGCAUUUGUUGAAUUGGGACAAAAGGAACAUUUUCUAAAUCAGCUUGAUACUCUUUAUAAAAAACAGCUGAAUCUUAUCUUCUGCCUCACAUUAAUUCAUGUGGCAUGCCAAAAGUUAGACUGAACUUUUCUACAUCUUCACCUUGCAUUGAUACAGGAAAGUCUUCUCUUUAAGUCUUGCUAAGUAUAAGGGGGAUAGUGGUCACGGGAAGAGGAGAACCGGGGCUGCUCUCGGAUGGUAAUUGACAAUGCCGAUUUCCAUUUCUUUGUCUUACGGCUACUUCCGAGCCUUCUAGCAAGGUCCCUGGUUGCAUGUAUUUCCUAAGAGCAGAGUUUAUUUCUCUUUACAUUCCCUGCUUCCUUGCUCUCCAUGCAGGGACCCCAGCCAACCUCUGGGCUGUUGAAUAGCUCUCUGCUGGGUGGCAAGCCCUUCUCCUUGGCACCCUGUUGCUUAAGCAUACAGAUUGCUCACCAGGUGCACACAGACAGCUGUACUGUCCAAGCCCAUUCUGCUCCACCCUGUCCUCUUCAGCUAAAGAGCAUUCCAGUAAUCUAAAGCCCUUUUCCCCUGGAGAAGUCCAGAGUUUGCAGCAGUGUGGAGCUGAGCUUGAACAGAACAGACCCUCAGCACGGCCCUGGACUAAUGCACUCUUAUCUGAGGGCAGUCCAUUCUAGAAGGUUGAUGAAUUUCCCUACCACUCUCCUGGGGACCUUUUCUCUCUAGUGGGAACAAAUGCUACAUAAUUUAGUCAAGAUCCUAUUAAGUCAUCUCACCUGAGGCAUCUGGAGAGGGAGUUGCCUUCCAUUGGUGGGAAAUUGUUGGUGCCAGAAUACAUUUUGCCCAAAACUCUUCUCAUUGGCUGGCCACCUAGCAGGGCUCCUCUAAACACGCAACUCAGCGAGGGGACCCCCUUCACCUCUGGCAAGAGAGCUGGGUAGAUCAGAAACUUGGUGACACCUGGCUAGCACAGAGCAGGCUCACUUGUCUUGGUCCCACUACCCAGAUUCCUGCAGACAUUGCAAACCAAAUGAAGGUUGUUGAAUGACCCCUGUCCCCAGCCACUUGUUUUGUUAUCAUCUGCUCUGCAGUGGAAUGCCUGUGUGUUUGAGUUCACUCUGCAUCUGUAUAUUUGAGUAUAGAAACCGAGUCAAGUGAUCAUGUGCAUCCAGACACACUGUGUCACCUGAGCCACAGAGCAAAUCACCUUAACGAUCUGGAAUGAAACUGUGACCAGUGCCGCCCUGGGUGGUUCUGGAGAGACUGCCGUCUUCUUGUUUGGCCAUAGGUGCUGGGGCCCCGGCUUCAGUCACUGUCUCAGACAGGAGUCCCGAUAAGCAGAUCACCAGUCCUCCACUGUCCUUCCUGUCGGCCUUGCUGCAUGAGAAGAUAGCUGCUUCCUCCCUCUUUUCCUACACUGUAAUUAUUGUUUUACAAUUGAGUGCCUUAAUAAUAGUUUACAAAUACUAUGUAUUUAUGCAAAACUGUUAAAGUCUCAUCUGUUAUGAUUGGAUACUUGGUCUUGUCAGUAGUGGUCAGCAUUGGGUUGUGAGCUUGUCCUACUCCAUACGUGUUUAUCCUGCUAUGCAGUUUUACAUUGUGUGUUCACAUCUAUUCCAAGGAGCCUUGCUAGAAACAACACUGGCGGUUCCUGCAGGCCAGGCAGGCAUUGGCCCAUGCUGUGUCCCAUAGGAGCCAAUGAAAGAACGUAGCUUGGUCUGCUAGCCAGCCGUGGGGUGGCGCAGGCCAGGCAGCCUCUGCACCAGAGUCCAGCACCUGCCCAUUCCCCAGUCACACAAUCAUACUCUUCUUUCAUAGAGAUUUUAUUACCACCUAGACCACCCUAGUUUUCCUCUCUGUUAGUGUCCUGAGCUCUUUUGCAACAAAAUGUAGGUACAGACCAAUCCCUGUCCCUUCCCCAAUCAGGAGCUCCACACCAUGAGUUGUUUGGUUUUCCAGAAGCUGCCAGUGGGUUCCCGUGAAUUGCGUUAAGAUAUCGAUGAUUUUUUUUAUUGUUUUUCUUCUUGUUUUUUUAAAUAAUAUAUUUAAAGGCAGUAUCUUUUGUACUGUGAAUUUGCAGUAGAAGAUGCAGAAUGCACUUUUUUUUUACUUCUGUUGGUGUGUAUUGUAUAUAGUGUGUGUGCUUCUUGUGAUGAAAAUAAACUUUUUCUUUAUAAAUUCCUGAUGACUGAGUUUAUAUAAAAGGAAACUGCUUCCUCAGCCCUUGCCAAAACAGUCUGAUACAUCGUCAUCAUCAUCGUCAUUGACAUGGCCAGUCUUUAUUGAGCAUCUAUUACAUGCUCAGUUCUUUGCUAGAAAACCUGGACAAGUUACACCAAAGAAAGGACCACAGGAAGAAAUGAUAGUUCCUCCUGGAACUAGUCUGUUUUCUUUCUAAUUUUGUCAGUAAGCAAGAACAGGCCCACCUGUGGGUGGUCCUUUGUGUACCAAAAAAAAAAAGUUACCCACCAGGAAAGGAUUUGGACUUUGGGUGGGUUCUCUUCCCGUACAAGUAGGAAAUGUAAAGCCAGAGGUGUGCACUAAAGAACAUCUAACCUGCUCCCACCAGCCCUGGUGGGAGAGGGAGGACCCUGGAGGCUAAGUACUGCUGGUUUCCAAGGUGCAUGCUCAUGUCCCAGUCCACUUCACCCCAGGCAGCUUUUGGUGGCUCUUCUCCCUUGGACACUCAGGAGGCAGAGCUGCUUCCAUUUUUUUUUUUUUAAUUUUUUUUUUUUUUUUUUUGAGACUGGGUCUGGCUCUCUUGCUCAGGCUGGAGUUCAGUGGUGCCAUCAUAGCUCACUGCAACCUCGACUUCCUAGGCUAAAGUGAUCCUCCUGCCUCAAGCAAUCCUCCCACCUCAGCCUCCCCAGUAGCUGGGACUACAGGCGUGCACCACCUUGCCCCGCUAAUUUUUACAAUUUAUUAUAGACAUGAAGUCUCGCUUUGCUGCCCAGGCUGGUCUUUAAUUCCUGUCUUCAAGUGAUCCUCCCACCUUGGCCUCCCAAAGUGCUGGGAUUACAGGUGUGAGCCACCUCAACUUCCAUCUUAAAAUUCUGCCUCCUUAGAGUUCUUUGCUUUCUGCUGUGUAGUCAGGGAGGAGUCACAUUCACUCAGUCUCCUCUGUCUGGAUGCGAUACAUCAUUUCUACUUGCUUUCCAGUGGGCAGGGCCCAGUCACAGGGUCCCAAUGCAACAGCCAGGGAGACUGGGAAAUGUAUGGGGCACAUGUAUUUGGUGAGCACUAACUGUCACAAGUACCUGGGCGUGACCCCUAAAUUCCAGUGCCUGCAGAGCCAGGAAGUAUUUUGUUCAGUUCAUCUGGACUUGCUCUGUCUCUCAACUGGACUCAAAAGACUGAUGAAUAAACCAGAAUGCAAGUUUAUUACUUUACCAAAAGAAUUAUAAUCAUCAAGCAGACCAGAUUGCUCACAUGCUGAUUAGCACAUUUAGUCCUGCUAGGUAAGUCUUUCUUUUUUUGAGACAGCCUGGAGUGCAGUGGCAGUCAUGGCUCACUGAAGUGUUGAUCUCCUGGGCUCCAGCAAUCCUGCCUCAGCCUCCCAAGUAGCUGGGACCAGAGCCACACACUGCUGCACCCAGCUAAAUUUAUUUAUUUAUUUAUUUAAAAGAUAGGGUCUCACUAUGUUGCCCAGACUGGUCUUGAACUCCUGGUUUCUGAUGAUCCUCCUGCCUCAGCCUCCCAAAGUGUUGAGAUUAUAGGCAUGAGCCACUGUGCCCAGCCCCUUCUAGGUAAAUCUCUAUGGGGUGCCAAAUUUUGGUUAAGAAUUGCUUAUUGAAUAUUAAAAGUUUAGUGGGAUGCUUCUUUUUUUUUUUUCUUUUGAGAUGGAGUUUAGCUCUUGUUGCCCAGACUGGAGUGCAAUGGUGUGAUCUCAGCUCACCGCAACCUCUGCCUCCUGGGUUCAAGUGAUUUUCCUGCCUCAGCCUCCCGAGUAGCUGGGAAUACAGGCAUGUGCCACCACGCCUGGCUAAUUUUGUAUUUUUAAUCGAAAUGGGGUUUCUCCAUGUUGGUCAGGCUGUUCUCAAACUCCCAACCUCAGGUAAUCCACCCGCCUUGGCCUCCCAAAGUGCUGGGAUUAUAGGCAUGAGCCACCGCGCCAAGCCACAGGAUGCUUCUAAUAGUGUUAUCAAGCUAUAAUGCAGCCCUCUCUGUAAAAUGUUUUAAAAACAAAUCACUGAGGGUCAUGGUUCAAGACACUGUUCUCUGGCAAGGUUGAAGAUAGCUAACAAAUUCUCUUUGGGUUCCAGCCAUGAAUGGGGUGGGAUGGGCCCCAGCAAUCUGUAUGUUUCUGAGAUUCCCUGGGAAUUCUGAUGGCCAAGUUUAGAAACCAUCAAAAUAAGAAUAUGAUGCAACUGAGUAGGCUCACGCUUUGCUAAUUACAUUGCACACAUGCUUUUUGGAGACAACACCCACACUACCCUAACAAUGUGUGUUCAUAAAACUCAUCCGAUACUUAUUUGUUCAAGGCCCUAGGACAAUAUUCCUGUAAUGGGCUGCUUUUGCCCUGAUUUCCUCCUCAGAGUAACUGUCUCGCGGUUGGGCACGAUCCCAGAUCACAUCUACAGUGGAGGUGGUUUUGCUGGGGAGGAUCCGCAUGCUUGUUUGUGUUUAUGCCUGGGGAACCCCCUCUUGGCAAGAUGUUCGGGAGAGGCUCCAAAGGCAGCACAGAGGACGGCUUGGAACUUAGGGGGAUUCACUUUAUGGUAAAGAAGCCCUUUCUAAAGGAGAGCUCCACCCAGGAAACACCACCCACCCACGCAUCCUUGCCUCCUAAAACCAGGUUAUGUUUAUCACAUACCUUCUAUGUGCUUUACAUAAAGAAUCCCCUGGAAUUCUCCAAACUGGGCAUUGUGGUCUGUGAUGCAUAUCUCAAAAGAGGUGAGAGGGUUGGGCACGGUGGCUCACGCCUGUAAUCCCAGCACUUUGGGAAGCCAAGGCAGGUGGAUCACUUGAGGUCAGAAGCUCAAGACCAGCCUGGCUCACAUGGUGAAACGCCGUCUCAACUAAAAAUACAAAAAUUAGCCGGGCAUGAUGGCGGGCGCCUGUAAUCCCAGCUACUCGGGAGGCUGAGGCAGGAGAAUCGCUUGAACCCAGGAGGUGGAGGUUGCUGUGAGCCAAGAUUGCACCACUGCACUCCAGCCUGGGUGACAGAGUGAGACUCUGUCUCAAAAAACAAAAAAAAGAAAAAAAAAGGUAGAGGAGAGUCCUUUUUCUAACUUUCUUGAACUCUUUGGACUACCUUGGGAUCCUUCUAUUAACUGCCUUGUUGGCAUUAUUCUCAGUUUAUGAAAAAACAGGCCCACAGAGUGGAAGUAAUUUGCCUACAGGUACAUCUAAAAAUUGAUGAAGCCAGAUAGGAACUGCUCCCUCAUCAUCUGAAACCCUUCCCAGAGCUGUCUCUCCCACCCCAGAAGUAGAAAGAAGCCAGACAAAGAUGCAUCUUGAUCUCCCUUGUGGUUUCAGCAAGGAAGCAGAUGAGUUGGAGAUGAAGCCCCCAGCCCCUGGGAAAUUGGACCCACUUCUUGCUCCAAAGGCUAUUGGGGUGACACAAGGUGUGUUUCUUUCCCGUAGAUCAUAUUCACCAUAUUUUGCCUUUAAAUGGAAAUUGUGCAUCCUGAAGUACCUUGUUAAGAGUCCAUUUUCAACCUGAAAUUCCUUUUUUUUGUAAACCACUUCAGCAAAUACAGUGUGGCAUUUACAUUAGCAACCUCCCAGCCUAGGAGAGGAUGCUCCAGCAUCCGACUCUAAAAGACAAAUUUGGGCACGGUGGCUUGACGCCUGUUAUCCCAACACCUUGAGAGGCCGAGGCAGGCAGAUUGCUUGAGCCCAGGAGUUCAAGACCAGCCCAGGUAACAUGGUGAACCCCCAUCUCUACCAAUAAUACAAAAAUUAGCCAGGCAUGGUGGUGUGCCAGUGGUCCCAGCUACUUGAGUGGCUGAGGUGAAGGAUCUCCUGAGCCUGGGAGGCAGAGGUUGCAGUGAGCCGAGAUCGAACCACUGCACUCCAGCUUAUGCAACAGAGCAAGACCGUGUCUCAAAAACAAAUAAAAAUAAAAGAUUUUAAAAAGACAAAUUAUCCCACAAAUGGUACAUUGUGGUGGUGGUGGUGGUGGUGGUGGUAGACCUCCCUCUUGCUCUUGAAAUUGGAUCAGAACAAACUGACAAUGCUACCUACUUCAUGGGGUCAUUGGUGAAUUCACUGAUAAUGCAUGCAAAUCCCCUUCUGCCUGGCACACUACCUAAUAAAUAAAUGGUGGUUGUUAUUGUUGGAAUUGGAGGAUAUAUUCCUAGUUGCAAGGGUUUCACAUGUAUUACCAAGUUAAUCCUCACCGCAGAUAUGAUUCUGUUUUACAGAGGAAGCAGUGGAUGCUCAGAGAGGUUAGGUAACGUGGGUCAGGGACACACAGCCAGGAAGGGGCAGAGGCUGGGAGUGCCUGACUCCAAAUUCAUGCAAUUUCUACCCCACCAUCUUCUCCCCAAGGAAAAUAGUCCCUAAUGCAUGUGUGCAAUGCUUAGAGGGCAGUAGAUGCUCAACAGAUGCUGAGAGAGUGAGGGAGUAAAUGAGAUAUGCCAUGAAAAGGAGCCCCUGUGGACUUAUGCGUGCGUUUGUUUAACUUGUGGGCAAGUACUUAUAGACAGGUGCAAACAAUAAAUCUCCUUUUGCAACUGA